GACAGCACGGUAACUUCCGGAAAAGUCCUGAACCUCAGUGGAAAAGCCUUGCAAGAAACAAUAACAAACGGGAGGAGGAAGCGAUUCUGGGGUUUCUGUGUUGAACGGUUCUUGUCCGCGAAGAUGCGCUUCGGCCUCUGUCAGGGGACUUGAACGGGCUUAGUGGGCUUCAGCCAGCUUUUCUCCACCGGUUCCCCACGGGGACCCCCCCCCCCCCCCGGCCGUUGCAAUGGCGGGCGUGGGGCCGGGGGGCUACGCGGCGGAGUUCGUGCCACCGCCAGAGUGCCCCGUCUUUGAGCCGAGUUGGGAGGAGUUCACAGAUCCGCUCAGCUUUAUCGGCCGCAUCCGGCCUUUGGCGGAGAAAACCGGCAUCUGCAAAAUUCGGCCGCCCAAGGACUGGCAGCCUCCAUUUGCCUGUGAAGUAAAAAGCUUUCGUUUCACUCCAAGAGUCCAGCGCCUGAAUGAACUUGAGGCAAUGACCAGAGUGAGAUUGGAUUUCUUGGAUCAACUAGCAAAAUUUUGGGAACUUCAAGGAUCUACUCUGAAGAUCCCUGUGGUAGAGAGAAAAAUCCUGGAUCUGUAUGCUUUGAGCAAGAUUGUUGCCAGCAAAGGAGGUUUUGAAAUGGUCACCAAAGAGAAGAAAUGGUCUAAAGUGGGUAGUCGCUUGGGAUAUCUGCCAGGAAAAGGAACUGGGUCUCUUUUGAAGUCACAUUAUGAAAGAAUUCUCUACCCAUAUGAGCUUUUCCAGUCUGGUGUGAGCCUUAUGGGUGUGCAGAUGCCUAAUUUAGAUCUUAAAGAAAAAGUGGAGCCUGAGGUUCUCAGCACUGAUACCCAAACUUCCCCAGAGCCAGGCACAAGGAUGAACAUUCUGCCGAAGAGAACAAGACGUGUGAAGACUCAGUCAGAAUCUGGAGAUGUGAGUAGAAACACGGAACUGAAGAAACUUCAGAUUUUUGGGGCUGGGCCCAAGGUUGUGGGCUUGGCAAUGGGAACAAAAGAUAAAGAAGAUGAGGUCACCCGAAGACGAAAAGUUACCAACAGGUCAGACGCAUUUAACAUGCAAAUGAGACAACGGAAAGGCACUCUCUCUGUUAACUUUGUUGAUCUCUAUGUUUGUAUGUUUUGUGGUCGGGGAAACAAUGAAGAUAAAUUGCUUUUGUGUGAUGGAUGUGAUGACAGCUAUCAUACAUUUUGUCUAAUUCCUCCACUACCUGAUGUGCCCAAAGGAGACUGGAGGUGUCCUAAAUGUGUCGCCGAGGAAUGUAGCAAACCUCGAGAAGCCUUUGGAUUUGAACAAGCUGUACGAGAGUAUACACUUCAGAGCUUUGGAGAGAUGGCAGAUAAUUUUAAGUCUGAUUAUUUUAAUAUGCCAGUCCAUAUGGUUCCCACAGAACUAGUAGAAAAGGAAUUUUGGCGGCUGGUAAGCAGCAUUGAAGAAGAUGUUAUUGUGGAAUAUGGAGCAGAUAUCUCCUCAAAAGACUUUGGAAGUGGAUUUCCGGUGAAGGAUGGGCGGAGAAAGAUUCUGCCAGAAGAAGAGGAAUAUGCACUUUCUGGUUGGAAUUUGAAUAACAUGCCUGUCCUGGAACAGUCUGUUCUUGCACAUAUUAAUGUGGACAUCUCUGGUAUGAAAGUGCCGUGGCUCUAUGUGGGAAUGUGCUUCUCUUCUUUUUGCUGGCACAUUGAGGAUCACUGGAGUUAUUCCAUCAACUACUUGCACUGGGGGGAGCCAAAGACAUGGUAUGGUGUGCCAUCUCAUGCUGCAGAGCAACUGGAGGAGGUGAUGAGAGAGCUGGCCCCCGAGUUAUUUGAAUCCCAGCCUGAUCUUCUGCAUCAGUUAGUUACCAUCAUGAACCCCAACGUGCUAAUGGAGCAUGGUGUGCCUGUGUACAGGACCAAUCAGUGUGCUGGCGAGUUUGUUGUGACAUUUCCUCGUGCCUAUCACUCUGGAUUUAACCAGGGCUACAACUUUGCUGAAGCUGUGAACUUCUGUACUGCUGACUGGUUGCCCAUUGGACGUCAAUGUGUAAAUCAUUACCGACGCCUAAGGCGCCACUGUGUCUUUUCACACGAGGAACUAAUUUUCAAGAUGGCAGCAGAUCCAGAAUGCUUAGAUGUGGGGCUGGCUGCCAUGGUCUGCAAAGAAUUGACUCUCAUGACUGAAGAAGAAACACGAUUAAGAGAGUCUGUUGUACAGAUGGGUGUCCUGAUGUCAGAAGAAGAAGUGUUUGAACUUGUUCCUGAUGAUGAGCGGCAGUGUUCAGCAUGCAGAACCACAUGUUUUCUCUCUGCUCUCACAUGUUCCUGUAAUCCUGAGCGGCUUGUAUGUCUCUACCAUCCAACUGAUCUGUGCCCCUGCCCCAUGCAGAAGAAAUGUCUUAGAUAUCGCUACCCAUUAGAAGACCUCCCUUCUCUGCUAUAUGGUGUAAAAGUCAGGGCACAGUCCUAUGACACUUGGGUCAGUCGUGUUACAGAAGCAUUGUCUGCUAACUUCAACCACAAAAAAGAUUUGAUUGAAUUGCGAGUAAUGCUGGAAGAUGCUGAGGAUAGGAAAUACCCAGAGAAUGAUCUCUUUCGAAAACUCAGGGAUGCUGUAAAAGAAGCUGAGACCUGUGCUUCUGUGGCUCAGCUGCUUCUGAGCAAAAAGCAGAAACACAGACAGAGCCCAGAUAGUGGGAGGACUCGGACCAAACUGACAGUGGAAGAAUUGAAGGCCUUUGUCCAACAACUUUUUAGUCUUCCGUGUGUCAUCAGCCAAGCUCGGCAAGUAAAGAAUCUGCUAGAUGAUGUGGAAGAGUUUCAUGAACGUGCUCAGGAGGCCAUGAUGGAUGAAACCCCAGAUUCUUCCAAACUCCAGAUGUUGAUAGAUAUGGGCUCUAGUCUCUAUGUGGAACUCCCUGAAUUACCACGACUGAAGCAAGAGCUACAACAGGCUCGGUGGUUGGACGAAGUAAGACUGACCUUAUCAGAUCCGCAACAAGUCACUUUGGAUGUCAUGAAGAAGCUGAUAGACUCUGGGGUAGGGUUGGCACCCCACCAUGCUGUGGAGAAAGCAAUGGCUGAACUACAGGAGCUCCUUACAGUCUCUGAACGAUGGGAAGAAAAGGCUAAGGUCUGCCUACAGGCAAGACCGAGGCACAGUGUGGCAAGUUUAGAAAGCAUUGUGAAUGAAGCCAAGAACAUUCCAGCCUUUCUACCCAAUGUGUUGUCCUUGAAAGAAGCCUUACAAAAGGCUCGAGAAUGGACCGCUAAAGUGGAAGCUAUUCAGAGUGGCAGCAAUUACGCUUAUUUGGAGCAGCUUGAGAGCUUGUCUGCGAAAGGACGCCCUAUUCCUGUGCGUCUUGAAGCACUGCCGCAAGUGGAAUCACAGGUAGCAGCAGCACGGGCAUGGAGAGAACGGACUGGGCGGACGUUUCUUAAGAAGAAUUCUAGCCAUACAUUGUUACAGGUGCUGAGCCCCCGGACCGACAUUGGUGUAUAUGGGAGUGGCAAAAAUAGGAGGAAAAAAGUAAAAGAACUAAUAGAAAAAGAAAAAGAAAAGGAUCUGGACCUGGAGCCUCUGAGUGAUCUGGAGGAAGGAUUGGAGGAAACCAGAGAUACAGCCAUGGUGGUGGCAGUUUUCAAAGAACGGGAGCAAAAAGAGAUUGAAGCCAUGCAUUCUCUCAGAGCAGCCAACCUAGCCAAGAUGACAAUGGUGGACCGCAUAGAAGAAGUAAAAUUUUGCAUUUGCCGCAAGACAGCCAGUGGGUUUAUGCUACAGUGUGAGCUCUGCAAAGACUGGUUCCAUAACAGCUGUGUUCCUCUUCCUAAAUCAAGUUCCCAAAAAAAAGGAUCCAGCUGGCAAGCUAAAGAAGUAAAAUUCCUUUGCCCUCUUUGUAUGCGGUCUCGAAGGCCCAGGCUAGAGACUAUUCUGUCACUCCUGGUAUCCCUUCAGAAGUUGCCCGUACGGUUGCCUGAAGGAGAGGCCCUGCAGUGUUUGACAGAACGUGCUAUGAGUUGGCAAGAUAGAGCGCGGCAGGCUCUAGCCACAGAUGAACUAUCCUCUGCCCUGGCCAAACUAUCUGUGUUGAGCCAGCGUAUGGUGGAACAGGCGGCUCGAGAAAAAACUGAAAAGAUCAUCAGUGCAGAACUCCAAAAAGCAGCUGCCAAUCCAGACUUACAGGGACACUUACCUAGUUUCCAGCAGUCUGCUUUUAACCGGGUGGUGAGCAGUGUGUCAUCUUCUCCUCGACAAACAAUGGACUAUGAUGAUGAAGAAACAGACUCUGAUGAAGACAUUCGAGAGACAUAUGGCUACGACAUGAAGGACACAGCCAGUGUGAAGUCCUCUAGUAGUCUUGAACCCAAUCUUUUUUGUGAUGAAGAGAUUCCCAUCAAAUCCGAGGAGGUGGUGACCCACAUGUGGACAGCACCUUCAUUUUGUGCAGAGCAUGCUUAUUCUUCUGCUUCUAAGAGUUGUUCUCAAGGUUCUAGCACCCCAAGGAAACAACCUCGGAAGAGCCCUUUGGUGCCCCGAAGUUUGGAACCUCCAGUGCUGGAGUUGUCACCUGGAGCUAAGGCACAACUGGAAGAACUUAUGAUGGUUGGAGAUCUCCUGGAAGUAUCUCUGGACGAGACUCAACACAUAUGGCGGAUUUUGCAGGCCACACACCCACCCUCUGAAGACAGAUUCUUGCAUAUCAUGGAGGAUGACAGCAUGGAAGAGAAACCACUAAAAGUGAAAGGAAAGGACUCUUCAGAGAAGAAACGGAAACGGAAGCUAGAAAAGGUAGAGCAACUUUUUGGAGAAGGAAAACAGAAGUCCAAGGAGUUAAAGAAAAUGGACAAACCUAGAAAGAAGAAAUUAAAAUUAGGUGCAGACAAAUCAAAGGAGCUGAAUAAACUGGCCAAGAAACUAGCAAAAGAAGAAGAGAGAAAGAAAAAGAAGGAGAAGGCUGCUGCAGCCAAAGUUGAACUUGUGAAAGAGAGCACUGAAAAGAAAAGAGAGAAAAAGGUGCUGGACAUCCCCUCAAAGUAUGACUGGUCAGGAGCAGAGGAGUCUGAUGAUGAGAAUGCUGUGUGCGCAGCACAGAACUGCCAAAGGCCCUGCAAGGACAAGGUAGACUGGGUACAAUGUGAUGGUGGCUGUGAUGAGUGGUUUCAUCAAGUUUGUGUGGGUGUAUCUCCAGAAAUGGCUGAAAAUGAAGAUUACAUCUGUAUAAACUGUGCAAAGAAGCAGGGGCCAGUUAGCCCAGGUCCAGCACCACCUCCUUCCUUCAUAAUGAGCUACAAACUACCAAUGGAGGAUCUUAAAGAGACCAGUUAGCAGAUGCUUGGUUAGUUUGGGACAUGGGGGGACAUGGACCACAUUGAGACCUUAGUCAUCAAGUAGAGUGGUUUAUAUCCACUUGGAAUGUUGCUUCCAAAGAUGAAUGGCCUUCAGAGAAAGUCCCCUUAGUGCUGGCUUCCUCUUUGCAUGGACUCUGUGGGUUACAUUCUCUAUCAACAUAUCUAUGCAGAGGGUGUCUUCUUUGGUACAACAGCCAAUAUUUCAUGUCUCCUUUGAGUGUGGUUUACUGCAUUAAGGCCAGAUGCUUAAUUGAGCUCUAGGGUGGCUGGUUAGUAUUAAUACAUUGGUGUGCUAACAGGGCAUAUAGGAUGUGGCUUUUGUCCAGCUGAUAGUAGUUAGAGGCUUACAACUUAGGAGCAGCACCAACUGAAGGUGCUAAUUGCUUGGAUCUCCUUCAUUGGGAUAGUUGGAGAGGGAUUGGAGUACCACUUUCCUUCCACUGUUACCUGGUACUUAAUGCCCUAAAGAUACAACUAGGAGUAACAGGGCCAAAGUUAUUUCUGUUAGACGUCAAGGAAUGGUAUCACAGUCUAUUGACCUCAGCGAUUUGUGCUUGUUUGUGCUAGAAGAACAUCCCAAAUAGGAGAACCUCUCACAAGCUGGGGCAGGUCACCUUAUCUUUGUAAGAUGAGGAUAUCAUCUAGAUCAGAAAUCUGACUAGAUUGGAUUCUGAGGAGAAGAACCUACUACAAGGCAAGGAGCCGUUUUUUGGCUUUGAAAAGUCUUGCUGUCUUGGGUCUACAUUUUAGGGAAGAGCAGGUACAUGGAUCCAGGCUUCUGCCAAAAAAAAAAAGAGAAGAAGAUGACGAUGAUGACCAGUCGUACUAUCUUACUGAGCCACAGUGAUGCAUGCUUUUCGGGGAAAACUUCAUUCACAAGUAUUCCAGACACCAGGCUUCAGGCAUGGCCAUGAGCAAGACCAGCAAAUAACAGCUUUUUGCCUUGCAGCCCUGACCCCAAUGUCUGCUGUUUCCAACACUGGUGAUUUCUAACUACGGCCCACAGCAGAUGCUGUUGAAUAACACCAUGGCUUCAUCAGAGGAUGUGGGGUUGUAGUACCUCUGGGUGAUGAAGUUGUUUUAGUAAAUCCAUUUUUAAAAAAAAAAAAGGACUUGUUUUUACUUUUUUCUAAAUGUCUCUGACUACUGACUGUUCUAUACAUAGAUUAUUUUUCCUUUUUUAAUAUACAUAUAUGAAUAUAUAAAUAUAUAUAUUUACUGUUACCAGCAGCAUAUGACAGAGUUUCAACAUCAAAAAUCCAUUUGGGGGCUUGCUUUUUCUUUUUUGCUUUAAAAAAAAAAAUCCCAUUCCUUCUUUGUAGUACAAGGAGUUAGCACUCCCUCCUCCAUCCCAGCCUGACCAGAUCUUCCAUUUUGCUUUUGUUCAUAUAGAUAAUUAUAUGUCCUUUGUGUGUUGGGACUUGUCCCUGUCUGUUGGGAAACUUGGUCUCACUCUAGUCUGUGCUGGCUCUUUUUUCUUUUGUGUGUGAAUGUUUGAAACUAUGGUGCUGUGUCCUCUUCCCUCCUGUUGUGUUCUCUGUUCUUCUUAAGGUAUUAGGUAAGCUGUAUGUAAACUCUUAUUAGAAGGGGACUAAUUUUUUUUUAAAGGACAAAAAAAAAAAUGACUAAAAAUAGUGUUUUGUCAUCACUGUCUGGUGUCUUUAUUUUGGUUUAAAAAAAUCUGUGGUUUGACUUAAAUUCAUCAGUUUUCCUUUUAAAGGGGGGAUUGGGGUGGACCUAGCAACAGCUUAUAGUUUCCUCUUCCCUUUUUGCCCCAGUCUCUUUUAAAGAACUGUCUUCUAGUAACUAGAAGUGAAAUGUACUGUCCAGUUACAGUUUGAGUGGGUAUGAGAUUUAACUCAAAAGGAAUCUUACAAAAAAAAAGAUGUUUUCUUAUAAAAUCCAAUUUCUGUAAAUGUUUUCUCUGAAGUUCAUACUACCUACUUUUUAUUCAUUCUUAAUACUGUAUAACAUUUUGAGUGUUUUGACUUGUUCAGAGGUUUGUUAGUGUUGCUGUGCAUAUGUCUUGAGGUCUCAUCUGAAGUAAGUUUGUGUAUGAUCGAAGAUUUCAAUGGAUAUUGCAAGGUAACUAAUUAACUGAUUUCAUAAGUUUUCGUUUUGCCAAGCUAACGAUUAUCAAUUAAGAAUUUCCUCUGGUUGAUGUUAUACAAGAAAGCACAAUAUUUUUUGCCUGUUGAUCUUCUUUGUAACAGUCUUCAGAUAUUUGUGGGUUAAAAAUUGAAUGUAAUUUUAAGUGACAGAUGCCUGGAAUACAUUUAAAAUUUUUAUUUUUCCUUCCUAAUCAUCCAUUAACUAUUCCACUAUCAGUGGAGAGUCAUGAGGAUGCUGAGAAAGUAUGAAUAGCUUCCUGUCACCUUCUGACGUUUUGAAACUUAAAUAUGUCUUUUCGUUGAUACUGUGGGAUUUUCUGUAUUUACUUGACAGUCAUGGAGGAUUUGGUAUGACUUGACCACAGGUUUAGACCAAGGCUGAGAAGAACAGAAGGGAGAAAUUAAUGGCAAAACAAAAAAUACACAAAUCUGCGGUUUUGGAAUUAAUGAAACAAGAUUCAUCUAUUUAAAGAAAUGUUGGUGUUCUAAUACAAAGCAUUAUUUUCACUUAGAGAAAAUUACUUACUUGCUCCCUUCUGUAUUGUAAUAUUUUGUAUUAAGACAUGAUUUAAAAUGUCUUUCUACCCUUAUCUCCUCUAAACUGCAACUGAAGUUGCAAUUCUUCAUCAUUAGUAUUUUAACUCUGGCAAAGGUUAUAGAAAGAAAAAUGGAAAUAUGGUAGGCCUGUGGUAUUCUUAAAAGCUAAGUCAUUAGAACUAUGCAGAUCCCCAAGUUUAAAAGUACAAAUACAGCACCAGUAGUUAGCUUUCUAGCUGGGGGAGAAGACAGGAGAUUUUUCUUCCACAGAUGUUUAUUUUGCUUCCUGAUAGGUACUGCAGCAAAGCCAUGUUGAUGUGUAGAUGCAUGACUUCCUCACUAAGCUGCUGCACACCAGCUUUGCCUGCAUGAUUCAAAUUUGUGCCUCAGUAAAAUUAUAAAUUAUUGCAUGUCAUACCUUGAAUAAUGGAAACGGCAAACAUUAAACCUGUGAUUACCCAUAAUGUACUUUAAUAAUAAAAAACAUGGCAGCCAGGUGCAGUAGAGUGCACCUGUGGUCAGGAGGCUGAAGUGGGAAGAUUGCUUCAACCUGUGAGUUUGAGUCCCGCCUGGUCAACAGCGAGACCCCAUGUGUCUGUCUGUCUCUCUCUUUUUUUAAAGGACAGAGGCUAAGCUGUAAGGUUAGCAUGGUUCUGCCUGGGCUUUGCUUCUGUGCUUCUGUGCAGGCUGAGCUGUAAGGUUAGCAUGGUUCUGCCUGGGCUUUGCUUCUGCGCUUCUGUGCAGGCUGAGCUGUAAGGUUAGCAUGGUUCUGCCUGGGCUUUGCUUCUGCGCUUCUGUGCAGGCUGAGCUGUAAGGUUAGCAUGGUUCUGCCUGGGCUUUGCUUCUGCGCUUCUGUGCUAGCAGGUGCCCACAAAAUGUCUUUUUGAAUUUCUUAAUUUUUGGGUUCUGGAUGCAAUUCGUGCACGCCAAGAAACUACUUGCUUGUCAGUAUUUUAAUUCUGUAGUACAUGUGUGUGAAUAUCAGCCAGUACUUACAGUAGGAGGAUGAACAGAAAAACUGAGAAGACCUGUCUUUCAAAAGAUGGGUUUAUCCACUUUUUAAGGGAAAAAGUGACAGUUUGGCAUGGGAUUUGAAAAGUGGAAAUUGUGGAAAAAUUGAGCUGUUGAAGUCCCACAUAUAACCAGAUUUAAUAAAGCUUCACAUGUGAAUUAGCUCCAUAUGUGUGUAGAAGGUUGCUUUUAUAGCAGGUCCUUAAGUACUCCUUUUGAAAUUCCUCCUUUUUUUUUAAGUCAUACCAUUACUUCUUUGGAUAUGAAUGUCCCAAGUGGUAUCUCCUACUGUAGUAUGAGGAAGAAUGGCUGUUAAUGUAUUUUUUGAAUUUUGGUCUUGUCUUGGCCUGGAUCAUAUCCAGUCACCACUAUGCAACAAAUGAUGUGCACUGGGCAAGGAUAUGAUGGGUUAUGAAAGCUGUAUCUUGUUUGUUUUUUCUUUUGCAGUACUCCAAGUGGUCUAAACAGGAAUGUCUUGUAAAACCUCAAGACUCCCUAUUGAUUAUUCCCUUACAUAUUUAUUUACAAUUUAUCAGGGUAAUUGGUGGUGCCUUAUGAAAAGUAUAACUCGAUUUCUUGAUCUUUGAGCAUGUUUUGUGUUUCUUGUGUUUUCUAAAAGAAUAUUAGAUAUGGUUAAUUGCAUUACAUCUAAAAGAUUUAAAAAAUUGUGUGUAUGCUCAGGUUCCCCACACCCAUACCCACCCUAACCCCUGUCAUUUACAUUGGUGGCAACUUUAAAUGGUAACCAAGCAAAAGUACAUUUUGAUAAUGAGUAUUGAUAAUCCUGAGGAAAACUAGUGAGUAUAUGGGAGCCACCUUUGACCUGUGCCAAAGCAGUUUCUAAUUUCAUUUGCUAACUAUAAAAUAAAGAACUGAGCCAAAAUAAUUUGAUCAGUGGUGUGAUUAGCCUAUUAUCAUUGCUGAGAAUAGUGUUUUUGGAGUGUGAAGUGAUUCCUGAAGAUUUCACCUGCCUUCUGUUUCCAGCAAGAAUCCAGUGAUGACCAACACAUUUCCUCACUUUUGGUUCUUGAGAAGUUUAUCCCUUUGCAACAAACCAUUAAUAGGGAAAACAAGGAAAUGCUUUCCCUUUCUCUUUGGCUUCUUAAAGCUCACAACCAAUUCAGACCCCAAGUUACUUCAGAGAAGCAAAUGGCACCUUUUCCCCAUUGCCAAGGAUCCCAGCUUAUGCAGAUAUGAAGGACGGAUCAUUUCUGAAAAUGUUAAGACUCUGCUUGCAGUGGACUUGGCCUCAGUUUCAUGAAAUGUGUAACUCUGUAUGUGUAUGUUAGGAGGAGGGUUGGUUGAAAGAGCGGGGGCAGGGAGGGGAAUCUGAUUACCUCUUGGGAAAUAAUUUUCUUGCCAACAAAAAGAUACACUUGAAGUUUCUUAAGGUGGCAAGUCCAUUAAAAAAAAAAAUUGUGUUGGACCCUCCCAGUUUAGAUCAAGUAUUUCUUGGGGGUCUUGCUAUUGUGGUUGAUACCAAUAAAUGGAAGAUCCAGAAUAUUUUCAUUUAAAGCUCAACCAUUAAUUGGAACAUGGUGAAACAUUGUACACAUUGUAAAAGUAGGGAACAGUACAAAAGAAUGGAAUCAAAUACUAUAUUAUGUGAAUAAACUAGAGUGAUUUUGGAAUUUCACUCUCUUCACCCCUUCUCACUUGUAUGUUCUGUAAAGUGUAUUUCUACUUUGGUAGGAAGAAAGACUUGAUUUAAUAUUUC